CCCCUAACCCUGAGGCUGCCGCGCGGCGGUCACUGCGCCGGGGUAGUGGGCCCCAGUGUUGCGCUCUCUGGCCGUUCCUUACACUCUGCUUCAGGCUCCAGUGCAGGGGCGUAGUGGGAUAUGGCCAACUCGGGCUGCAAGGACGUCACGGGUCCAGAUGAGGAGAGUUUUCUGUACUUUGCCUACGGCAGCAACCUGCUGACAGAGAGGAUCCACCUCCGAAACCCCUCGGCGGCGUUCUUCUGUGUGGCCCGCCUGCAGGAUUUUAAGCUUGACUUUGGCAAUUCCCAAGGCAAAACAAGUCAAACUUGGCAUGGAGGGAUAGCCACCAUUUUUCAGAGUCCUGGCGAUGAAGUGUGGGGAGUAGUAUGGAAAAUGAACAAAAGCAAUUUAAAUUCUCUGGAUGAGUGGAGAAAGAAACGUCACACUGCCUUUCAGAAUCAGGGAAAUCACCCUUGCAAGCACAAGACAAGAAUGUGGGAUAGAGACCCCAAAAUUCCUGUUCAGAACCUAAGCUUAGCUCUCUGUUGGCAGGCCCAAUCAGGUCAUGGCACCUGUAAUAGAUUAUUUGCAUGGGUGCAAAAGAAAAUGGUUUGCCGCUGGAGUAUCAAGAGAAGUUAAAAGCAAUAGAACCAAAUGACUAUACAGGAAAGGUCUCAGAAGAAAUUGAAGACAUCAUCAAAAAGGGGGAAACACAAACUCUUUAGAACAUAACAGAAUAUAUCUAAGGGUAUUCUAUGUGCUAAUAUAAAAUAUUUUUAACACUUGAGAACAGGGAUCUGGGGGAUCUCCACGUUUGAUCCAUUUUCAGCAGUGCUCUGAAGGAGUAUCUUACUUGGGUGAUUCCUUGUUUUUAGACUAUAAAAAGAAACUGGGAUAGGAGUUAGACAAUUUAAAAGGGGUGUAUGAGGGCCUGAAAUAUGUGACAAAUGAAUGUGAGUACCCCUUCUGUGAACACUGAAAGCUAUUCUCUUGAAUUGAUCUUAAGUGUCUCCUUGCUCUGGUAAAAGAUAGAUUUGUAGCUCACUUGAUGAUGGUGCUGGUGAAUUGCUCUGCUCUGUCUGAGAUUUUUAAAAAUCAGCUUAAUGAGAGUAAUCUGCAGACAAUUGAUAAUAACAUUUUGAAAAUUGGAAAGAUGGUAUACUGUUUUUAGAGGAAUAAACGUAUUUGUGGUUUAA